AGUCCUCCCAAAGUACUUGUGUCCGGGUGGUGGACUGGAUUAGCUGCGGAGCCCUGGAAGCUGCCUGUCCUUCUCCCUGUGCUUAACCAGAGGUGCCCAUGGGUUGGACAAUGAGGCUGGUCACAGCAGCACUGUUACUGGGUCUCAUGAUGGUGGUCACUGGAGACGAGGAUGAGAACAGCCCGUGUGCCCAUGAGGCCCUCUUGGACGAGGACACCCUCUUUUGCCAGUUCAGGGCUCCCAGACUCGAGUCAAGGGGGCCCAUUCUCAGGACUCCCAGAAUACACCAGCAGGCCCCCAGUCUGAGAAAGAGACUUAUGACCUUAAGGUUGCAUGCCAGGAAGAUGUCUUUUGAUUUCAAGCCAUCAUCGCAAAAGAGGAGCUUUGUCUUUAUUGUCACUGAAGAUUUUUGUUUGGAAGAGAGCAUCAUGAAUGAUGAUGAAAUGAAAAAUGCAUCAAGGACAGAUCGGACCCCUGAGGAGACAGCAGGACCUCCUGCACUGACCCCUCCUCAAGAUCCCCACUCGGCUCAGGCUCUGACCUUGGCAAGAGAUCCCCCAGAGAAGGCACUCCUCUUGUGGGCAUUUGGUCUACCAGGGAACUCUUAAAGAUUGGACUCAAUGCCUAAAGGUAUUAAUCUAUAAGGGAGGAAUUUUAUGUACUGUGACAAGCUGUGAGACAUUGUUAAGAGUAACGCUUCUCGGGAAUCAGACCUUCCCUGCUUCUGAGAUACCCCAGACAAGACCAGCAAAACCACCGACGGUCCCAACCCUGGGCUCAGUCGCAGAAUGGAAAGAACCAUGAUUCUCCAAACCUGCAGCCAGGAGGUGAAUCCACUCAAAAAACCCCACCUGCUGCUGCCAUCCAGUCAGCCCUGCAAGCUCCCCUAGGGAUGGGAGCUGCUGCUCAAAGCGUCCUGCUUUUUGGUGUUGAAAAGCUCCGUUCUUCAGAAAGUACAUUCUUACCCCGAGGCCCUGCUGCUCUUCUUGAACACCAACCCUACCUGUUGUAGUGCGGAUCCACGAGGUGCACAAACUAGUCUAGUUUCUCAUCUUCUUUGUGGUCAUUCAUGUGUGUGGUGACAGGUGCCAUGCCCUGCCCUGCCCCUUCAUCCCCAGCUCCCCCCAACCUGGGCAGUCAUCCCCAGUCCUUCAACCUCUCUCAGGGGCCUUGGUCUCUCCUGUUUAAAUACAUUUCUUUUAGAGACA